CAUUUCUUUUUUUUUUUUUUUUUUGAGGCAGAGUCUUACUCUGUCAUCCAGACUGGAGUGCAGUGGUGCCAUAUUGGCUUACUGCAACCUCUGCCUCCCAGGUUCAAACAAUUCUCUUGCCUCAGCCUCCGAAGUAGCUGGGAUUACAGGCAUGUGCCACCACACCUGGCUAAUUUUUGUAUUUUUAAUAGAAAUGGGGUUUCACUGUGUUGGUCAGGCUGGUCUCAAACUCCUGACCUCAGGUGAUCCACCCGCCUCUGCCUCCCAAAGUGCUGGGAUUAUAGGCGUGAGCCACCGUGCCCAGCCACCUCUGGAACUUCUGACUGUCCAACUUCAAGUUAGGGUUCCCAUGACUCCCUCUUUGGGUUUGAAUGAUUUGCUAGGGAGGCUCACAGAACUCAGGGAAACACAUUUACUGGUUUAUUGUAAAGGUUGUUACAAGGGAUACAGUGAAGAAUACAUGAGGUAAGCUAUGGGGAAGGAGUGUAGAGCUUCCGUGCCCUCCCCGGGUACAACACCCUCCAGGAACUGCCAUGUGUUCCGGAAGCUCUCCCAACCCUGUCCUCUUGGGCCUUUUAUGGAGACUUUAUUGGAUAGGUAUGAUUGACAACCAUGUAGAAAUGUGACUGGACAAAAAGGGUAUGAACAAACACUAAUAGACUGCAUGAGGGAAACCCAGCAAGGCCUGUCUGUUCAGAUCCUUCUGGCCUCUCUGUGCAGCCUUCCUUCUUCCAGGGUUUGGGGCAGGACCCCUUCUGAAAUGGGAGUCUUGUGACCUACAAUCAGACAGGAAAUGCAAUGGCACAUCGUGAUUCUGAGAUGAAAGAAGAAUGUCUAAGGGAAGACCUGAAGUUUUACUUCAUGAGCCCUUGUGAAAAAUACCGAGCCAGACGCCAGAUUCCGUGGAAACUGGGUUUGCAGAUUUUGAAGAUAGUCAUGGUCACCACACAGCUUGUUCGUUUUGGUUUAAGUAACCAGCUGGUGGUUGCUUUCAAAGAAGAUAACACUGUUGCUUUUAAGCACUUGUUUUUGAAAGGAUAUUCUGGUACAGAUGAAGAUGACUACAGCUGCAGUGUAUAUACUCAAGAGGAUGCCUAUGAGAGCAUCUUUUUUGCUAUUAAUCAGUAUCAUCAGCUAAAGGACAUUACCCUGGGGACCCUUGGUUAUGGAGAAAAUGAAGACAAUAGAAUUGGCUUAAAAGUCUGUAAGCAGCAUUACAAGAAAGGGACCAUGUUUCCUUCUAAUGAGACACUGAAUAUUGACAACGACGUUGAGCUCGAUUGUGUUCAAUUAGACCUUCAGGACCUCUCCAAGAAGCCUCCGGACUGGAAGAACUCAUCAUUCUUCAGACUGGAAUUUUAUCGGCUCUUACAGGUUGAAAUCUCCUUUCAUCUUAAAGGCAUUGACCUACAGACAAUUCAUUCCCGUGAGUUACCAGACUGUUAUGUCUUUCAGAAUACGAUUAUCUUUGACAAUAAAGCUCACAGUGGCAAAAUCAAAAUCUAUUUUGACAGUGAUGCCAAAAUUGAAGAAUGUAAAGACUUGAACAUAUUUGGAUCUACUCAGAAAAAUGCUCAGUAUGUCCUGGUGUUUGAUGCAUUUGUCAUUGUGAUUUGCUUGGCAUCUCUUAUUCUGUGUACAAGAUCCAUUGUUCUUGCUCUAAGGUUACGGAAGAGAUUUCUAAAUUUCUUCCUGGAGAAGUACAAGCGGCCUGUGUGUGACACCGACCAGUGGGAGUUCAUCAACGGCUGGUAUGUCCUGGUGAUUAUCAGCGACCUAAUGACAAUCAUUGGCUCCAUAUUAAAAAUGGAAAUCAAAGCAAAGAAUCUCACAAACUAUGAUCUCUGCAGCAUUUUUCUUGGAACCUCUACGCUCUUGGUUUGGGUUGGAGUCAUCAGAUACCUGGGUUAUUUCCAGGCAUAUAAUGUGCUGAUUUUAACAAUGCAGGCCUCACUGCCAAAAGUUCUUCGGUUUUGUGCUUGUGCUGGUAUGAUUUAUCUGGGUUACACAUUCUGUGGCUGGAUUGUCUUAGGACCAUACCAUGACAAGUUUGAAAAUCUGAACACAGUUGCUGAGUGUCUGUUUUCUCUGGUCAACGGUGAUGACAUGUUUGCAACCUUUGCCCAAAUCCAGCAGAAGAGCAUCUUGGUGUGGCUGUUCAGUCGUCUGUAUUUAUAUUCCUUCAUCAGCCUUUUUAUAUAUAUGAUUCUCAGUCUUUUUAUUGCACUUAUUACAGAUUCUUAUGACACCAUUAAGAAAUUCCAACAGAAUGGGUUUCCUGAAACGGAUUUGCAGGAAUUCCUGAAGGAAUGCAGUAGCAAAGAAGAGUAUCAGAAAGAGUCCUCAGCCUUCCUGUCCUGCAUCUGCUGUCGGAGGAGGAAAAGAAGUGAUGAUCACUUGAUACCUAUUAGCUAAAGUUCUGCUAAAGAUGAUUAAAGUUCAGGCAUCCUUAUCCAGCGGCUGAGCAGAGGAACCCCAAAUGACUUGGACAAGCAGUUCCAAAAUGACUCUCUUAUUUAAUUGUGGAGUGGGAAAGAGGACUCACAGUUAGCCAGCUGACCAUGACUGAAGUUCCAGCUUUACUUUUUAUAAACUUGAAUGAUAAAGAAUAGACCAUGGGCUACUACUGGGCAUUAGUGCAAUAUAACAGCGAUAAUAAAAUUCUCUAUUAGUCUGUUAAUUUAUGACAUGAUCUCGGAAUGGAAAAAGAUCAUUUCAGAGUGUGCGAAAUAAUAGUCUUUAACCAUGUAAUUAAAUAUGUGUGUUUAUUGUCAAAUAAGGAUUUGUUUUAAAGGUGAUUCUUGGGUUUGAAGACAUUUGUUAAUUCAUGGUCUGUACAGAAAUGAAGCUGGUUGCAAUACCAAUCUAGAGAGUCCAAGCUGGUGAACUAUUAAGCUGUUUAAAGAUCACCCUUGGCCUGGCACAGUGGUUCACACCUGUAAUCCCAGCACUUUGGGAGGCCUAGGCAGGCAGACUGAGCUCAGGAGCUUGAGACCAGCCUGGGCAACAUGGCAAAAACCCACCUCUACAAAAAGUACAAAAAUUAGUCGGGCGUGAUGGCAGGCAUCUGUAGUCCCAGCUACUUGGGAAGCUGAAGUGGGAGGAUCACCUGAGCUCUGGAGGUGGAGGCUGCCAUGAGCCAUGAUCGUGCCACUACACUCCAGCCUGGGUGACAGAGUGAGAUCCUGUCUCAAAAAAAAAAAAAAAUCACCCUUAAAUCAACAAAAAGACCUCAUGCUCAUGCAGUGGACAUUUCUUGGCCUGUUUUCCUGUGGGUUUUCUUCAGCAUGAUAUGAAGCAACUGUUGGCAUAGCCAGUGGGAUAAAUAAGAAAUGGAAUCAUUUGGCUGCCUCGUCACUUGUGCUAAUGGUCAGUUGUACACACAUGACAUGUGGAAGUGACCUGUAGCAGCGGUCACUCAUUUUAACAAUUGAACUCUGCUGGGUUGGGUAUUUACCUUUGUCUAGAAAAGAAAUAUGAUAUAUUUUCUCUAAAUAAAUUUAUUUUCAUCAUUCCA